CUUUAAGAAAGUAUUGAAGUAUAACACAUAGAGAAAUGUAUGCAGAUCGCAAAUGUACAGCUUGAUGACUUUUUGCAAACUGAACAUAUCUAUGUAACUGGCACCUAGAUCAAGAACCAGUACACCACCAGUGCCCUACUUCUGGUCACCACCCCACUCCACCCUCAGUGUGUUUGAAACACCUCACAUUUUAUGUCCAGGGUAAGUCCUUCAUUUACAGAAUUCUAUGUUUGCCUGAACCAUUACUUUAUAUGAGCUAGCUACUGUUAGCUUACAUCAAGGUGUCUCCCUUGUCACUGAAAAUGUGUAGACGUCUGCCUAAGUAAAGAUUACAAUGUUAAAUUUGGGCACUGAGUGUACAUCAAUAUUUAUGUGUUUGUGAUUUCCAGGUACACAAAUACAUACAUGGCAUGCAUACCAACAAAUCUGGAACUACUUUCUUCUUAAUGAAUGUAAAACUGAAUUAUGCUAUAUUGAUCUAAGCUUAGAAUAUCUUUAACUACAAUUGAUUGCCACAGAAUAUUUCAUGUGCCCUGUUUCCAGUUUUUUAAAAUUGCUCAUUUCAGUUACCAUAAGUAUUCCUUUUGAAUGCUCAAGAUUUCAAAGCCAAGAAUUUUUCAUCUUCUGUUUGAGGUAGAAUUGUAUGUGUUUGUCCUGAAUAUCCACAGCUGUCUUUUUAUAUGGUUCAAUUUCUGUGUCUGAUACUCAGAAAAACAUCAUUUUGAUUCCUGUGGGGUUUUUUUUAUGUGAGAGCUUGAGUCAGAGAAAGAAACAGGUUUAGCAGGCUCUCUAUGCUUUAUAUAUACAUAUAGUUUUGAAAAAACAAUUUAUGUGUUAUCAAAAAUCAUGUAUUAUUAUUGGGUUGUAUAAGUGUACUCUUAGAAGUGAAAAUCAAGGGUUAUACUUAAUAUACCCAUUAGUUUUUUAAAAAGCUAAAACGUCUUUCUCAUUAUAGAAGUAAUAUGUCUAAGAAUAUUUUUCAGCCAUAAAAAGUAAUGGAGUAGUGAAAGGUGCUACAAUAUGGAUGAAAAUUGAAAAUACUAUGCUAAGUGAAAGAAGACAGACACAAUAGGCCACAUAUUGCAUGAUUCCAUUUAUAUGAAGUGUCCAGAAUAGGAAAAUCUGUAGAGACAGAAAGUAGAUUCGUGGUUGCCAGAGCUGGGGAGAACGAGAAUAAAGAAUGACUGCUAGUGGGCACAAGGUUUCUUUGGGGGAUAAUGGAAAUAUUCUGGAAUUAGAUCGCAGGAAUGGUUGCACAACCCUGUUAAUAUCAUAAACACCACUGAAUUGUAUACUUUAAAAGAAUGAGAUGUGUAGCACGUGGAUUUUAUCUCACAUUUUUUUAAAAAAAUAAGACGUGCAUUGUAGAAAAUUUGGAAUCAAAAGAAAAGUAGAAAAUGGCAGGAACAAGUUAUAGCCUCAUUGUCCAGCAACAAUUACUGUUGCUUUCUAGUGUAUUUCCUUUCAGUUUGUUUUGUUUUUCAUGUAUUGUUGUUGCAGAGGGAAGACUUCAAUAUUGCUUCCUGUUACAUGACAGAGAUACAGUUAUUAAAUGUUAAAUAGUCACAUAUUAAAAUCAACCCAACCCCCUUAAAAAAGGGCAGGUCCCAAGAAAGAUUCGUUUAUUUGUCGGAGGGAAUAAUGGAUGGGAAUGCCAAUAAGACAAGCAGAGAAUGAUGGCUAGCCCUGUAAGAAGGGAUGAAGAAGAACCUGAAGGGAAGAGAUCCCAGGUCCUGAGAGGCAGAAAGACAGAUUUGAGCAGUUGCCAUGAAAGAGUUUCAUAAAUGGACGCUGACAUGGACUACGAAAGACCCAACGUUGAAACUAUCAAAUGUGUGGUCGUGGGUGACAAUGCCGUGGGGAAGACGCGCUUGAUCUGUGCCAGGGCGUGCAACACCACACUCACGCAGUAUCAGCUGCUGGCCACCCACGUGCCAACAGUGUGGGCGAUUGACCAGUACCGCGUGUGCCAGGAGGUCUUGGAGCGUUCUCGGGAUGUUGUUGAUGAAGUGAGUGUUUCUCUCAGGCUUUGGGAUACUUUUGGUGAUCAUCACAAAGACAGACGCUUUGCAUAUGGCAGGUCUGAUGUUGUGGUCCUCUGUUUUUCGAUUGCUAAUCCCAAUUCCCUAAAUCAUGUGAAAAGCAUGUGGUAUCCAGAAAUCAAGCACUUUUGCCCUCGAACACCCGUUAUCCUUGUUGGGUGCCAGCUUGAUCUCCGCUAUGCCGACCUGGAAGCUGUUAAUCGAGCCAGGCGCCCGUUAGCAAGGCCCAUAAAGAGAGGGGAUAUUUUGCCCCCAGAAAAAGGCCGAGAGGUAGCAAAGGAACUUGGCUUACCAUACUAUGAAACAAGCGUGUUUGACCAGUUUGGUAUCAAGGAUGUGUUUGACAAUGCAAUCCGAGCAGCGCUGAUUUCCCGCAGGCACCUGCAAUUCUGGAAAUCCCACCUAAAGAAAGUCCAGAAACCUUUACUUCAGGCACCCUUCCUACCUCCAAAAGCCCCUCCACCGGUCAUCAAAAUUCCAGAGUGUCCUUCCAUGGGGACAAAUGAAGCUGCCUGUUUACUGGACAAUCCUCUAUGUGCCGAUGUUCUGUUCAUCCUUCAGGACCAGGAACACAUCUUUGCACAUCGAAUUUACCUCGCUACCUCUUCUUCCAAAUUUUAUGAUCUGUUUUUAAUGGAAUGUGAAGAAUCCCCAAAUGGGAGUGAAGGAGCCUGUGAGAAAGAGAAGCAGAGCAGAGAUUUCCAGGGGCGGAUAUUGAGUGUCGACCCAGAGGAAGAAAGGGAGGAGGGCCCGCCUAGGAUUCCUCAGGCCGACCAGUGGAAGUCUUCAAACAAGAGCCUGGUGGAGGCUCUGGGGCUGGAAGCCGAGGGUGCAGUUCCUGAGACACAGACUUUGACCGGAUGGAGUAAGGGGUUCAUUGGCAUGCACAGGGAAAUGCAAGUCAACCCCAUUUCAAAGCGGAUGGGGCCCAUGACUGUGGUCAGGAUGGACGCUUCAGUCCAGCCAGGCCCUUUUCGGACCCUGCUCCAGUUUCUUUAUACGGGACAACUGGAUGAAAAGGAAAAGGAUUUGGUGGGCCUGGCUCAGAUCGCAGAGGUCCUCGAGAUGUUCGAUUUGAGGAUGAUGGUGGAAAACAUCAUGAACAAGGAAGCCUUCAUGAACCAGGAGAUUACGAAAGCCUUUCACGUAAGGAAAGCCAAUCGGAUAAAAGAGUGUCUCAGCAAGGGAACGUUCUCGGACGUGACAUUUAAAUUGGACGAUGGAGCCAUCAGUGCCCACAAGCCGCUGCUGAUCUGUAGCUGUGAGUGGAUGGCAGCCAUGUUCGGGGGGUCAUUUGUGGAAAGUGCCAACAGUGAGGUGUAUCUCCCGAACAUAAACAAGAUAUCAAUGCAAGCAGUAUUGGAUUAUCUCUAUACCAAGCAGUUGUCUCCUAACUUGGAUCUGGACCCGCUGGAAUUAAUUGCCUUGGCAAACAGAUUUUGCCUGCCACACUUGGUUGCACUUGCAGAACAGCAUGCCGUUCAGGAGUUGACCAAAGCCGCCACGAGUGGCGUGGGCAUUGACGGAGAAGUGCUCUCUUACUUGGAAUUGGCUCAGUUUCACAAUGCCCACCAGUUGGCCGCCUGGUGUUUGCACCACAUCUGCACCAACUACAACAGUGUAUGCUCCAAGUUCCGUAAGGAAAUCAAAUCAAAAUCUGCAGACAACCAGGAAUACUUCGAGCGGCACCGCUGGCCCCCUGUGUGGUACCUGAAGGAAGAAGAUCACUACCAGCGUGUGAAAAGGGAACGAGAGAAGGAAGAUAUUGCACUAAAUAAGCAUCGCUCAAGACGAAAGUGGUGCUUCUGGAAUUCAUCUCCAGCAGUGGCCUGAAGAGGAAGAGAAAAAAAACAAAAAACAGAAACCAAUCGGUAAUCUGAUCCACCACUUUUCAAAGCACUACUAUAAAAUUCGUCUUGUUAGAGAUACGACAUAGUUCAGGUUUCGGGCACUGAUCUUCCUCCACUUUUGUGCAUUUAUCUUUGUUAGGAUCAAAGCACAAGCUCACCAUCAAUGAGCCUGGACAAAAAGGGAAGCUGACUCUCACUGCAUUCCUUAAACUGAUAUGUAUAUUUUUUUUGUUAGGAGGCUUAAUAAACUUUAGUCUGUUAUUUUGUUUCUUUUUAUACAAAGAAAAAAAAUUCAGCUUUCAUGUUUCUGAUUCCAGAUUGGAAAAUAUUUUUAUAUGGUCUGUUGUAUUUUGUUGAAAUGAAAAUACUGUGUAUUACUUUAUUUUACAGGCCACAAUUGAUUAUGAAGUCACCCUGUGAUUCUCUUUGCCCACAUGACCACCGAGCAUUAUUACGUAAUUAGAGGGUUAUCCUUUUGUUGUGAAAGGAAGGAGGGGACUGAAAUCUCCCAAAGUGCAAAUUGGAGAGUGUUUAAUCUUUGUUCUGUUGAAUAACAUCGGUGUAAUUACAAAGUCAACUCCAAGAAUGUGUAUUUACAAUAUUUGCCAUGUUAAGUGCUGGUAAUUAUAUGGUUAUAUGUGCCAUGUAAAAUAUAGUGAUAUCAAAUAUUCUGUUGUUUCCAAUGUCUAGUUUCAAGAGGACAAUCUUUAUAAUCAUUAGAAGGGCUUAUUAAAUCCCAGCAUUAUCCAGGGCAAACUCACUGGUGGACCUGAAUACAUAAGAUACCAUUAGUGCGCUGGUGUUCGGAUUGCUGUAUUAGGGUUUACAUCUCUCAGUAUUCCUUGAACUUGCCAUGCUUCUGCAUGCAGAUUCUUCACUGACUUGAAUUGAGAUGGGCAAGGGAAAAGGUCCCUGGACUCCCUCCUGCCAUCUACAGGCUUGUCACAUCUCACCACCAGAAACAGGCUUCCUCAGGCUUCUCACCUGUGGCCAACUUCACUUUGUAAGACCCAUAUUUUUAACUCUUCCCAGGGAAAAUUCAUGUUGCUGCAGAAGUAGGCUAAGGCAGACCACCCACUUCUGCUGAAAUGCAUUGGGAGCCUGUGAAAGCACAAAGCUGGAGGCUGGGCGCCUGCGUUCUCCUACACGGAAAGGAAUCUAAUUCCAAGAGUCUAGGAAAUGGUGCUAUUGUGAGUUCGUUCUGACUCUUUCUCAUUCUGAGUUUUCAGUGUUAAACUAGGAAGUGUGACAGCAGGGGAGCUUUCGUGAGGCAGUCAGUCAUUGCUUCUCUGUAAAUUAAAAUGUUACAGCACACACAUACACACACAGAGAGCAUUUCAAGGCCACAGCUCCACACCUGCCAUGGGAUGUUAAUGUGGCAGGGGGUGGGGCUCAUUCUGUUGGGAGGUCAAAUUACCAAUGCCAAGGACUGUUGAUUUUGUUUUUAUUUUUAUUUUUUCUUCUAGCUUUUCAGAAGAUGGAAAUGAGACAGUUGAGUCCAAACCCCAAUGCUGACAGCCAUAUGCAUUUGAAAAUCUAUCUAGAUUACAGAUGGGCAUUUAUUACUGGCAGUGGAAACACCAGAUAGAAGAUCUUAGGAGAGGCCCAGAAAUGCAUCACCUUGUCAUGACAAAAGAGAAGGCAGUAGAGUAGGGAUAGUUACAAAUGCAUCCAUCUUAAUUAUUUUCAAUAGGCUUGUAAAUCUUAUCGAUGGAAGGAGAAAGGAGACAAGAUGUGGAAGAAUUGACAUGUAUCCCACCAUAAAAUGGUAGAAGAUGAGUUUUCAAUGAGUAGUCAUAGUUGAAAUUUUACAACCAAAGCUCCCAUUUGAUUGUAAUCUUGCCAAAAUAUAAUGGAUGUAUAAAUGAACUUGGGGUAUAAGCAAUAAUAUCCACUAGUGUUGUUAUCAGCUACUGUAACCAAGUGGCUGGUUCAUUUGGUUGAUGCUGAUUAUGGCCUUUAACCAUGGUGGUUUGUUGUGUGUUUUUUAUUUCACAAAAAGCCAAUAAAAUUGUUUAGCUAUAAAA